AGUGGAGUGGCAGCCCCAGAACUGGGACCACCGGGGGUGGUGAGGCGGCCCGGCACUGGGAGCUGCAUCUGAGGCUUAGUCCCUGAGCUCUCUGCCUGCCCAGACUAGCUGCACCUCCUCAUUCCCUGCGCCCCCUUCCUCUCCGGAAGCCCCCAGGAUGGUGAGGUGGUUUCACCGAGACCUCAGUGGGCUGGAUGCAGAGACCCUGCUCAAGGGCCGAGGUGUCCACGGUAGCUUCCUGGCUCGGCCCAGUCGCAAGAACCAGGGUGACUUCUCGCUCUCCGUCAGGGUGGGGGAUCAGGUGACCCAUAUUCGGAUCCAGAACUCAGGGGAUUUCUAUGACCUGUAUGGAGGGGAGAAGUUUGCGACUCUGACAGAGCUGGUGGAGUACUACACUCAGCAGCAGGGUGUCCUGCAGGACCGCGACGGCACCAUCAUCCACCUCAAGUACCCGCUGAACUGCUCCGAUCCCACUAGUGAGAGGUGGUACCAUGGCCACAUGUCUGGCGGGCAGGCAGAGACGCUGCUGCAGGCCAAGGGCGAGCCCUGGACGUUUCUUGUGCGUGAGAGCCUCAGCCAGCCUGGAGACUUCGUGCUUUCUGUGCUCAGUGACCAGCCCAAGGCUGGCCCAGGCUCCCCGCUCAGGGUCACCCACAUCAAGGUCAUGUGCGAGGGUGGACGCUACACAGUGGGUGGUUUGGAGACCUUCGACAGCCUCACGGACCUGGUGGAGCAUUUCAAGAAGACGGGGAUUGAGGAGGCCUCAGGCGCCUUUGUCUACCUGCGGCAGCCGUACUAUGCCACGAGGGUGAAUGCGGCUGACAUUGAGAACCGAGUGUUGGAACUGAACAAGAAGCAGGAGUCCGAGGAUACAGCCAAGGCUGGCUUCUGGGAGGAGUUUGAGAGUUUGCAGAAGCAGGAGGUGAAGAACUUGCACCAGCGUCUGGAAGGGCAGCGGCCAGAGAACAAGGGCAAGAACCGCUACAAGAACAUUCUCCCCUUUGACCACAGCCGAGUGAUCCUGCAGGGACGGGACAGUAACAUCCCCGGGUCCGACUACAUCAAUGCCAACUACAUCAAGAACCAGCUGCUAGGCCCUGAUGAGAACGCUAAGACCUACAUCGCCAGCCAGGGUUGUCUGGAGGCCACGGUCAAUGACUUCUGGCAGAUGGCGUGGCAGGAGAACAGCCGUGUCAUCGUCAUGACCACCCGAGAGGUGGAGAAAGGCCGGAACAAAUGCGUCCCAUACUGGCCCGAGGUGGGCAUGCAGCGUGCUUAUGGGCCCUACUCUGUGACCAACUGCGGGGAGCAUGACACAACCGAAUACAAACUCCGUACCUUACAGGUCUCCCCGCUGGACAAUGGAGACCUGAUUCGGGAGAUCUGGCAUUACCAGUACCUGAGCUGGCCCGACCAUGGGGUCCCCAGUGAGCCUGGGGGUGUCCUCAGCUUCCUGGACCAGAUCAACCAGCGGCAGGAAAGUCUGCCUCACGCAGGGCCCAUCAUCGUGCACUGCAGCGCCGGCAUCGGCCGCACAGGCACCAUCAUUGUCAUCGACAUGCUCAUGGAGAACAUCUCCACCAAGGGCCUGGACUGUGACAUUGACAUCCAGAAGACCAUCCAGAUGGUGCGGGCGCAGCGCUCGGGCAUGGUGCAGACGGAGGCGCAGUACAAGUUCAUCUACGUGGCCAUCGCCCAGUUCAUUGAAACCACUAAGAAGAAGCUGGAGGUCCUGCAGUCGCAGAAGGGCCAGGAGUCGGAGUACGGGAACAUCACCUAUCCCCCAGCCAUGAAGAAUGCCCAUGCCAAGGCCUCCCGCACCUCGUCCAAGAGCUUGGAGUCUAGUGCAGGGACCGUGGCUGCGUCACCUGUGAGACGGGGUGGCCAGAGGGGACUGCCAGUGCCGGGUCCCCCUGUGCUGUCUCCUGACCUGCACCAACUGCCUGUACUUGCCCCCCUGCACCCGGCUGCAGACACAAGGAGGAUGUGUAUGAGAACCUGCACACUAAGAACAAGAGGGAGGAGAAAGUGAAGAAGCAGCGGUCAGCAGACAAGGAGAAGAGCAAGGGUUCCCUCAAGAGGAAGUGAGCGGUGCUGUCCUCAGGUGGCCAUGCCUCAGCCCUGACCCUGUGGAAGCAUUUCGCGAUGGACAGACUCACAACCUGAACCUAGGAGUGCCCCAUUCUUUUGUAAUUUAAAUGGCUGCAUCCCCCCCACCUCUCCCUGACCCUGUAUAUAGCCCAGCCAGGCCCCAGGCAGGGCCAACCCUUCUCCUCUUGUAAAUAAAGCCCUGGGAUCACUGUG